GGAGGAGUCUUACCCUAAUGUAAGAUGGUGGCCCGUCUGGCUGUGGAACCCACCGAAAGCUGAGAGUCUCUCUCUCAGCCGUAAAGGUCGGACUCGCUGAAGCAAUCAGGCCCGGUUCUGAAGAGUUUUUUCCCCGACGCUCGUUCGGUGGUUUCUUGUGAGGACGCGGCAGCCCGUGGAGUCGGCUGAGGGAAAAGCGAGGCAAGGCAGGCGGGUCGUCAAAGUCCUACAUUUUAGCUUUCAGUGCUGAACUUCCUUCUCCCUUAAAUUAUUAUAAACUUUUGCUGCUGUUUAAUAAACGUGAAGAUGUCUCGCAGUCCUGAUGCGAAGGAAGACCCUGUGGAGUGCCCUCUUUGCAUGGAGCCCUUGGAGAUAGAUGAUAUCAACUUUUUCCCUUGCACCUGUGGCUACCAGAUUUGCCGAUUUUGUUGGCAUCGAAUUCGCACUGAUGAAAAUGGGCUUUGUCCUGCAUGUAGAAAGCCAUAUCCAGAAGACCCAGCAGUUUAUAAACCACUCUCCCAGGAAGAGCUGCAAAGGAUAAAGAAUGAGAAAAAACAGAAACAAAAUGAGAGAAAACAGAAAAUAUCAGAAAAUCGCAAACAUUUGGCUAGUGUACGUGUCGUACAAAAAAACCUCGUCUUUGUUGUAGGUUUAUCUCAGCGCCUAGCAGACCCAGAGGUUUUAAAACGACCAGAAUAUUUUGGGAAGUUUGGUAAAAUACAUAAAGUUGUCAUCAAUAAUAGCACAUCAUAUGCAGGCUCACAGGGUCCAAGUGCCAGUGCUUAUGUAACCUAUAUCCGGUCAGAAGACGCUCUCAGAGCCAUACAGUGUGUCAACAAUGUGGUAGUAGAUGGCAGAACACUUAAGGCAUCUCUAGGUACAACAAAAUACUGCAGUUACUUCUUAAAGAAUAUGCAGUGUCCAAAACCUGACUGCAUGUAUCUUCAUGAAUUGGGGGAUGAGGCGGCCAGCUUCACAAAAGAGGAAAUGCAGGCGGGUAAACACCAAGAAUAUGAACAGAAGCUACUUCAAGAAUUAUAUAAAUUAAAUCCCAAUUUUCUUCAGCUAUCUACGGGUUCAGUUGAUAAAAAUAAGAACAAAGUGACACCACUGCAGAGGUACGAUACCCCCAUUGACAAACCUUCAGAUUCUCUCAGUAUAGGGAACGGUGAUAAUUCCCAGCAGAUAUCUAACAGUGAUACGCCUUCACCACCACCUGGUUUGUCAAAAUCCAAUCCAGUCAUCCCCAUCAGUUCAUCCAAUCACAGUGCACGGUCCCCUUUUGAAGGGGCAGUAACAGAGUCACAGUCGUUAUUCUCAGACAAUUUUCGCCAUCCCAACCCUAUCCCAAGUGGGCUUCCUCCUUUCCCCAGCUCCCCACAGACAUCCAGUGACUGGCCUACAGCACCAGAACCACAGAGCCUCUUCACAUCAGAAACAAUCCCAGUAUCAUCCUCUACAGACUGGCAAGCAGCUUUUGGCUUUGGUUCUUCUAAACAACCAGAGGAUGACUUGGGUUUUGAUCCCUUCGAUGUCACUCGAAAAGCCUUAGCAGACCUGAUUGAGAAGGAACUGUCCGUUCAAGACCAACCUUCCCUUUCGCCCACAUCUCUUCAGAACUCCUCUUCACACACUACAACCGCCAAAGGUCCAGGCUCUGGAUUCCUGCAUCCUGCUGCAGCUACAAAUGCCAAUUCUCUCAAUAGUACCUUUUCAGUCUUGCCCCAGAGGUUCCCUCAAUUUCAGCAGCACCGAGCGGUUUAUAAUUCAUUCAGUUUUCCAGGCCAGGCAGCCCGCUAUCCUUGGAUGGCCUUUCCACGCAAUAGCAUCAUGCACUUGAACCACACAGCAAACCCCACCUCAAAUAGUAAUUUCUUGGACUUGAAUCUCCCGCCACAGCACAACACAGGUCUGGGAGGGAUCCCUGUAGCAGGGGAAGAAGAGGUGAAGGUUUCGACCAUGCCACUGUCAACCUCUUCCCAUUCAUUACAACAAGGACAGCAGCCUACAAGUCUCCACACUACUGUGGCCUGACAACAGAACUGAGAGGAGAGGAUUAGACUCUGGGGUGCUUGCAUGGGCAACUGGAUUUUUGCAUGAUUCCUUUAUGAUUUUGCUUUUAAUGUAUACACCCAGAAGAGCCAAUAUAAACGUUCCUCAUGCCUACAGCUAGCGUGUUACCUCAUAGUUGUUGAAGUAUUUCUUCAUUAGGCCUUUAACAUAAUUUAUUAGUGUAAUAAUUUUGGCAUUGUUUCUCAUGAGUGAUACUAUUUCUAACUCAUAAAAAUAAACUUGUAGUACUAAGAUCCCAGGUGAGAUUAGCUAGAAUUGUUGUUAUUUUGGCUCUAUUAUUGAAAAAUUAUACAAAGGUAAUGGUAGUAUCUUGUUUUCUGGUUUGUGAAAAAAUAAUAUCCUAAUCUCCUGAAAAAUUUGCAAAUUAACAAGAUAAUGUCUAUUGCAUUCUUUGAAUACUUGAGAAGAAAGAAUACAUAUAAAACAAAAUUGGUGGUGUCAUUUAAUGCUCAGAAGGAUAUUGUUGGCGAUUGUUUUUAGUUGUCUAGAUUUAUAUCCUAUAAUAUGCAUUACAUGUGUAGAAACUGUUUUGUUCUCUCUCUUUUGCACUUUUGCACUUUCUUUUUGAAUGGUUGUUAAUUAUGCAUAGAUGGUUAAAAGAUAAUUAUUGUAGCCUAAAUGCAAUAUAAUCUCUUUUCUAAUGCACUGCCUAGUAUACCAGGAAAUGCCUCAAAAACAGAACUUCAGUUUAUAGUUGACUUAUCUGAAACUUGAAUACGGAGUAAACAUUGUAUGUGAAAAGCAACCAUAGUAGUGUAACAUUGUUACUGAACAAACAGUAAUUCUGUGGGAUAUUGUUUUGGAAAUUUCAUUGUUUAAUAAUUAAAAUGUGAUAAUAAGAUAAUAUUAUAAGUACCUGACCAGAAUGAGACUAAGGCAGAAGAGAAGAGAUUGGAUGUCCUCUAAAAUUAGGCCACCUAAAUUGUAACAGAUAAUUUUAAUCAAGAGAAUAGUGGAGUACUUUAUUAGGACAUAAUGUGAAGUGAUAUUUCUGAAAACACAUUUCUUGAAAUAGUUUUAAAACUGAUAAUAAAGGAAAAGAAACUGUACUUAGUUUGGAGCAGUGGACAAAAGCUGAUUCAGAAAACAUGACCAUAUUCUGCCUACAUGAAGCAUCUGGGAAGAAAGGGAAAGUCACACCUCCUCUUGAGAUUUUAACCAUUAUGAUAAAAGGUAUGCUUUAAUUUGUUAAAAAAAAAAGUAUGAAAGGGGAUAAUGUGAAUACAAAAAAGAAGCCUAGAGAUUGAAAAUAAUAAUAAUAGAACAUGUUAUUAGGAGAUGGUACUUAAUGUCAUGUUGGAGUUGGAGUUUUCAAGGUUACCUCUAUAUAAAAUUGGAUUAUUUUCUGUUAGAUAUAAUGUGACAAAUUAAAUGACUUUAUCCCAAGGUACAGUGAGGUAAACAAAAAUCUAUUCUUAGAUAUCCUUAGAUUUGGUUAACUGAGGCUGUAGAAGCAGCGAAUUGUCUAGCCAUUUAAGUUAUUUUUGUAAAAUUCAGCAUAAACAUCAAUCUCUAAUUUCUAUCUAGAAGUGACUUUAAGACAUUACAAGAACAUUGCCAAUUUGGAAAAUGCCAAUAAAAUACUGUAGACUUAUUAAUAUUGUAGACUUAUUAUCAGUCUUUUACUAUAGCUUAAUUUAAUUAUGGUUUUCAUUUUUACUGUAAGAGGCCAAGACUUCACUUAU